CCGGAAGCCGGAGAGCUGGAGCUUUGAAGCCACCCCGGUCAAAGGAUGCUGAGUCCGGAGCGCCUAGCCCUACCGGACUACGAGUAUCUGGCUCAGCGACAUGUCCUCACCUACAUGGAGGAUGCAGUGUGCCAGCUGCUAGAAAACAGGGAAGAUAUUAGCCAAUAUGGAAUUGCCAGGUUCUUCACUGAAUAUUUUAACAGUGUAUGCCAGGGAACACACAUUCUCUUUCGAGAAUUCAGCUUCGUCCAAGCCACCCCCCACAAUAGGGUAUCAUUUUUACGGGCCUUCUGGAGAUGCUUCCGAACUGUGGGCAAAAAUGGCGAUUUGCUGACCAUGAAAGAAUAUCACUGUUUGCUGCAAUUACUGUGUCCUGAUUUCCCGCUGGAGCUCACUCAGAAAGCAGCCAGGAUUGUGCUCAUGGACGAUGCCAUGGACUGCUUGAUGUCUUUUUCAGAUUUCCUCUUUGCCUUCCAGAUCCAGUUUUACUACUCAGAAUUCCUGGACAGUGUGGCUGCCAUCUAUGAGGACCUGCUGUCAGGCAAGAACCCCAACACAGUGAUUGUGCCGACGUCGUCCAGUGGGCAGCACCGCCAACGACCUGCCUUGGGCGGGGCCGGCACGCUGGAGGGCGUGGAGGCGUCGCUGUUCUACCAGUGUCUGGAAAACCUGUGUGAUCGGCACAAGUACAGCUGCCCACCCCCAGCACUUGUCAAAGAGGCCCUCAGCAAUGUUCAGAGACUGACCUUCUAUGGAUUCCUCAUGGCUCUCUCAAAGCACCGUGGAAUCAACCAAGCCCUCGGAGCUUUGCCUGACAAGGGGGAUCUGAUGCACGACCCAGCAAUGGAUGAAGAGCUGGAACGGCUGUAAGUGUCAAGUGGGAGGAUACUGCCCCCUUGUGGGGGCCAGACGGGUCGGACACGGCUGUGCCCCAUCUGGGGCCAACACCACUUGUCUGUAACAUCCCACAUCUGCCAGGGAAGGGUCUGGGGGCCAGUGGAGGCCUGAGGUGUCCCUCCCUCUGAGUCCUUUGGGGGCUGCAGCCCAGGGGUUUACCCUAGUGUUAAGAGUGGGCAUGGAGGCCCUGCUCUCUGUACAGGAGGCCUCUCGCUGCCCUCCAGGCUUCUUCCCUUCUUCAGGCUGGCCCAGGUCCCAGGCCUGGUCAACUCGGUCACAGCCAGUCCAGAGGCCAGUUGCCUGCCUUCCCGGACCCCUCCCCGGGUUGGCUCUCCCUGGAGACCUCUCCAUCAUUCCCGAAAAGUGGAUGGAGAGAGUGAUGGCUCCACUGAAGAGACAGACGAGUCGGAGACUUGAGGAGUCCAAAGGGUCCUGCCCACAGCGCCCUGUACCUGCUCCCACCCAGCCCUUGGUGUGCCCACCCAGCCUCCUCUCCAGCACCUUGCUGUGCUGCCCUCUGCUGCUGACAAGGUGAAUAACAGCCCCAAGACCAGCCAGAGGGGCUCUGAUGAUCAGCCCAGCCAGUGGCCCCGGAAGGUGAAUGGCCUGCUCUCCCUGGCCCUAUCAGCCUGUGAACUUCACUUAGGCCCCAAGCUGACAGACUGUGCUGAGGCCACCUUGUCACGCCGUAGCCUGUUAGUCCUCCUAACCUCUUAAGAGCAGUCUCUUCUGAGCCAGCCUCUGCGGGUCCCCCAAUAAGGUUCAUCUCCUCACAGCAACUCCAUUAAGGGGGAGAACCCGAAUAGCCACGCAGGGCCUUGCACCAUCAAGGGUGACACCUGCGACGCAAGUACCAGGAGGACAUAACCGCUGUGGCCUGUUGGAGAACAGCCAGUAGCCUUGGUAAUAUGAAGGGUGGGCCAGAAGAUGAUUUCACUUGCAAAAACUGCUUCAAGUCUUGACCCCUUUGUGUCUAAUAGCUAAACAAACAUGUGAAACGAAUAAAAAGUCCCUCAUGUCUGGUAA